GGAGACUCGGCCGAGACGCGGGGGGAGGCGGCGGCGGCGGCGAUGCGGGGCUGCUGGAGGCGGAGAGGCACGGAGGAGCCGCUGGGGCUGCCGCCACGGCCGCCCGGAGCUGCAUGGAAAUCCCGGCGCUUCUGCUGUCUGGAGUCUGUGCUGUUUCCUCUGGCAAAUCACGGAGAUUCUGUUCCGAGCACCAACCCUUCCUCUUUGCCAUGCGCUCCACAACGCAGAGCAGGACGCCGAUUCCGAAGUUUGACCCGCUUGGGGCAAUUAGCUGGGAGGUGUCUACUUCUUCCUGUGGCGACACCGCUUCAGGGAUGGGAAGUGAGGAUUCCGGAAGAGUCUGAGAGAAGGCUGGAAGAAGGCUGGAGGGUGGUGUCAUGGGAUGCAUGUGCAGAUUCAGAAGUGGCAGGUGCAGAAGAAGAGCAUCCAGGACAAGCAGCUGUCUCUAUGCCACAUCAUUUGGCACCCUGCGAUGUCACCUUGCUUUUCAGGAGUGCAGCCGGACAGUGCUGAAACCCAUUCAUCUGUUGAUGGACACCGGCAUCUUAUUGAACAAAUACUUUUAGAGGACCUCCUAUGUUUAGGGCACUGUUGUAGAACCAGUGAAAGGAAGGAGAGCUGGAGUCCUGGGUCAAGCUGAGUAUCUCCACGUUUAGGUGCACAAAUACUAUUUUGUGAAGAUCUUAAAUUUGUGGUAUAAGAACUUGAAGGAAAUAGAACUGAUUUGUUACUUCUAAAAGAUUUGUAAGACUCCAGGGCCUCCCAGCCGUGAAUAAUCUGAUGGUUCCUGAAAUGACUGGGGAAGCAGACGCUUCGUAUGGCAGUUGAAGAGUGUGUGUCUAUGUGCAUUUAAAACCUUCUUUCUGUACUUACACAUUCACACGGGAAGACAGGCUCAUUCUUGUGCACACUUGAGAGUUUUACAACUGAUGAAAAUUAAUUUAAGAAUCAGAUGGAGCAACUUGACACCAGUGGGCUCAGGAGCCCGGGGAGAAAAAUACAUCACUAAUGGCCAGUUUUCCAUAUGGUCUGCACGGGUAAAGAAAGUCUGCAAAAAGAAGAAAAAAAAAUUUGCGCAGAUUAAACCACAAAAAUAUUCUCCAGUUUAAAGAAGGAACUAAGUGAGAAGGUGACUGAGAAAGAAGUGUGAUUUCAAACAUUGCAGCGGCUCACACAGUGUUUGUUGCACUUUAUUUUUCAGUGGGUUUGGUGAUUUGGACGGAUUAAAAUUCUAGACUGAAAAGUAACUCCUACUGUGGUUAUGGCUAGAGGAAAGCAAGUUCAAGUAUGAUGGGACAAGUUUGAAUAAUGAACUGAUUCCUUUGCCUAUCUUAAUUAACUGUAUUUGAGAAAUUUUAAUUUAUUAUUCCCCCCCUUUUUUCCUGCAUCUAUAGGAUAAUAUUGUAAAAUAGCAAUUGAAACCAAUAAUUAUUAAAUAAAUAUCAAGGAAAAUCCAAGCAAAGCUUUCUUUUUGUUGGACUAGUGGUGUGGUGUUUGGAGACAGUCUCUGAAUGUGAACAGGAAAGCACCCAUCAGCAAAACACUAUCACUCUCUAGGGAGACAGCUGGGGGAAUCUGACUCUGGCUUCUGCUUUUGUUUUAAGGGAUUAACUUCCCUGUCAAGUCCAAGAAGACUUGCGUAUGAGAAGAUUACCUGAUGGACUUAAUUCUAAGAUUAGCUUUUUUCAUCAAGAUGGAAAAAGAUCUUUAGGAGCAGAAAAGGGGAGUGCUAACUGGGGGAGCGAGAAGGGAGACGAGCAAAAGAAACAAAAUCUUGCCACGUGGCUCUGUUUUGUCAGCAAGAGGAUUUAAGACUCACCCAGGGCAAACACUGGGACCACUGUAAGAGCGCUGGAACAUUCUGCCUCUUGAGUGAAGGGGCCUUCUUUCUAGCCUCUAUGGCACUGAGGGGUGCGCCGGCUGGUGGAGGAGCAGUCCGAUGGAGCCCUGCGUUCCCCGGGGACACAGGGCCAAGCUUUGAGGUGGAAAGUUUCUGGUUCUGAAACAACAAGGAGAGAGUCUGUUUUUCUUCCUAAAAUUUGGACUCUUGUCUGCACAAACUCUGGUCUGUUUUGCACGGUUUGUGUGCCUUUUUUUCCCUUUAUGCAAUCUUUUUCAGCUUUAGCAGCAGAAAUUUGUCUAGUUCAGGAAACAUGCUAGAGGGUGGCUUCAGAAGGAAGAUGAUCCUGUGUAUUCUGUCUCUGCAUCCGAACUUUUGAAGAGAAAAAUUCGAGCUAGAGGGAUUCUUAAAGCCUUAAGUUACUUGAAAUCUAUGUAUUUGCAACCCUUUGUCUCUGGAAUCAUAUUACACUAAACUGGAAUCUCAGGCUGAAUGAGAAUAACCAAGUGGAGUAAAAAGAAGAAAACCGUUUCUUGAUCACCACUUAAUUAACGAUGCUCUUUCUCCAAAGGAUCAGCACGUUCUUCCUCUGAGAACUUGAAAAUACAAAUGGACCCCAUGUUUUUUUAAGCAUUACCUUUUCUUAGAAGACUGCCAUCAUCUUUUAUAGAGGAAUUUUUUCACUAUGCAUUCGGUGGAUCUUUAUAAAAUACUGACCUUCUAAUUAGAUUCAGGUCAGUCUUAAUUAAAGGGGGAAAAAAGCAACGCAAGCCAACCACAAAAACACAUAUACCAAUGAAAGAAAUUGGUUUAAAUUUCACAGCAUUAACAUUACUUUUUAAGUAAAACAGUUCAUUGAAGAAAGUAUGUAUGCAGCAGUGGAACAUGGGCCUGUGCUUUGCAGCGAUUCCAACAUCCUGUGCCUGUCCUGGAAGGGGCGUGUCCCCAAGAGUGAGAAGGAGAAGCCUGUGUGCAGGAGACGCUACUAUGAGGAAGGCUGGCUGGCCACGGGCAACGGGCGAGGAGUGGUUGGGGUGACUUUCACCUCUAGUCACUGUCGCAGGGACAGGAGUACUCCACAGAGGAUAAAUUUCAACCUCCGGGGCCACAAUAGCGAGGUUGUGCUGGUGAGGUGGAAUGAGCCCUACCAGAAACUGGCCACGUGCGAUGCGGACGGAGGCAUAUUCGUGUGGAUUCAGUACGAGGGCAGGUGGUCUGUGGAGCUGGUCAACGACCGCGGGGCGCAGGUGAGUGAUUUCACGUGGAGCCAUGAUGGAACUCAAGCACUUAUUUCCUAUCGAGAUGGGUUUGUCCUGGUUGGGUCUGUCAGUGGACAAAGACACUGGUCAUCCGAAAUCAACUUGGAAAGUCAAAUUACGUGUGGCAUAUGGACUCCUGACGACCAACAGGUGCUGUUUGGCACGGCCGAUGGGCAGGUGAUUGUCAUGGAUUGCCACGGCAGAAUGCUGGCCCACGUCCUCUUGCACGAGUCAGACGGUGUCCUCGGCAUGUCCUGGAACUACCCGAUCUUCCUGGUGGAGGACAGCAGCGAGAGCGACACGGACUCAGAUGACUACGCCCCUCCCCAAGAUGGUCCGGCAGCAUAUCCCAUCCCAGUGCAGAACAUCAAGCCUCUGCUCACCGUCAGCUUCACCUCGGGAGACAUCAGCUUAAUGAACAACUACGAUGACUUGUCUCCCACGGUCAUCCGCUCAGGGCUGAAAGAGGUGGUAGCCCAGUGGUGCACACAGGGGGACUUGCUGGCAGUCGCUGGGAUGGAACGGCAGACCCAGCUUGGUGAGCUUCCCAAUGGUCCCCUUCUGAAGAGUGCCAUGGUCAAGUUCUACAAUGUUCGUGGGGAGCACAUCUUCACACUGGACACUCUCGUGCAGAUCUCUUUGAGACCCUGCUUUUCAAGUCUUCUGGAUUUGUGCCCAGAAGUGGACUUGCUGGAUCAUAUGCGCCCCAUCAUCUCCAUCUGCUGGGGUCACCGGGAUUCGAGGCUGUUGAUGGCAUCAGGACCAGCCCUGUACGUGGUGCGUGUGGAGCACCGGGUGUCCAGCCUGCAGCUGCUGUGCCAGCAGGCCAUCGCCAGCACCUUGCGUGAGGACAAGGACGUCAGCAAGCUGACUCUGCCCCCCCGCCUCUGCUCCUACCUCUCCACUGCCUUCAUCCCCACCAUCAAGCCCCCAAUUCCAGAUCCGAACAACAUGAGAGACUUUGUCAGCUACCCAUCAGCCGGCAACGAGCGGCUGCACUGCACCAUGAAGCGCACAGAGGACGACCCGGAGGUGGGCGGCCCGUGCUACACGCUCUACCUGGAGUACCUGGGCGGGCUUGUGCCCAUCCUCAAAGGGCGGCGCAUCAGCAAGCUGCGGCCAGAGUUCGUCAUCAUGGACCCGCGGACAGAUAGCAAACCAGAUGAAAUCUAUGGGAACAGCUUGAUUUCUACUGUGAUCGACAGCUGCAACUGCUCAGACUCCAGUGACAUUGAGCUGAGUGAUGACUGGGCUGCCAAGAAAUCUCCCAAAAUCUCCAGAGCUAGCAAAUCACCCAAACUCCCAAGGAUCAGCAUUGAGGCCCGCAAGUCACCCAAGCUGCCCCGGGCUGCUCAGGAGCUCUCCCGGUCCCCACGGUUGCCCCUGCGCAAGCCCUCUGUGGGCUCGCCCAGCCUGACUCGGAGAGAGUUUCCUUUUGAAGACAUCACUCAGCACAACUAUCUUGCUCAGGUCACGUCUAAUAUCUGGGGAACCAAAUUUAAGAUUGUGGGCUUGGCUGCUUUCCUGCCAACCAACCUCGGUGCAGUAAUCUAUAAAACCAGCCUCCUGCAUCUCCAGCCGCGGCAGAUGACCAUUUAUCUCCCAGAAGUUCGGAAAAUUUCCAUGGACUAUAUUAAUUUACCUGUCUUCAACCCAAAUGUUUUCAGUGAAGAUGAAGAUGAUUUACCAGUGACAGGAGCAUCUGGUGUCCCUGAGAACAGCCCACCUUGUACCGUGAACAUCCCUAUUGCACCGAUCCACAGCUCGGCUCAGGCUAUGUCCCCCACGCAGAGCAUAGGGCUGGUGCAGUCCCUACUGGCCAAUCAGAAUGUGCAGCUAGAUGUCCUGACCAACCAGACGACAGCUGUAGGGACAGCAGAACAUGCAGGUGACAGUGCCACCCAGUACCCAGUCUCCAACCGGUACUCCAAUCCUGGACAGGUGAUUUUCGGAAGCGUGGAAAUGGGCCGCAUCAUUCAGAACCCCCCUCCACUGUCCCUGCCUCCCCCGCCGCAGGGGCCCAUGCAGCUGUCCACGGUGGGCCAUGGAGACCGAGACCACGAACACCUGCAGAAGUCAGCCAAGGCCCUGCGGCCAACACCGCAGCUGGCAGCUGAGGGGGACGCAGUGGUCUUUAGUGCCCCCCAGGAGGUCCAGGUGACGAAGAUAAACCCUCCACCCCCGUACCCAGGAACCAUCCCCGCUGCCCCCACCACAGCAGCACCCCCGCCCCCUCUGCCGCCCCCACAGCCCCCAGUGGAUGUGUGCUUGAAGAAGGGCGACUUCUCCCUCUACCCCACGUCAGUGCACUACCAGACCCCCCUGGGCUAUGAGAGGAUCACCACCUUCGACAGCAGUGGCAACGUGGAGGAGGUGUGCCGGCCCCGCACCCGGAUGCUGUGCUCCCAGAACACGUACACCCUCCCCGGCCCGGGUAGCUCUGCCACCUUGAGGCUCACGGCCACUGAGAAGAAGGUCCCUCAGCCCUGCAGCAGUGCCACCCUGAACCGCCUGACCGUCCCUCGCUACUCCAUCCCCACCGGGGACCCACCCCCGUAUCCUGAAAUUGCCAGCCAGCUGGCCCAGGGGCGGGGGGCUGCCCAGAGGUCCGACAAUAGCCUCAUCCACGCUACCCUGCGGAGGAACAACCGUGAGGCUACGCUCAAGAUGGCCCAGCUGGCCGACAGCCCGCGGGCCCCCCUGCAGCCCCUGGCCAAGUCCAAGGGCGGGCCCGGGGGGGUGGUGACACAGCUCCCAGCGCGGCCCCCACCUGCCCUGUACACCUGCAGUCAGUGCAGUGGCACAGGGCCCAGCUCACAGCCCGGAGCCUCCCUGGCCCAUACCGCCAGCGCCUCCCCGUUGGCCUCCCAGUCCUCCUACAGCCUCCUGAGCCCACCCGACAGCGCCCGCGACCGCACCGACUACGUCAACUCGGCCUUCACGGAGGACGAGGCCCUGUCCCAGCACUGUCAGCUUGAGAAGCCCUUGAGGCACCCUCCCCUGCCUGAAGCUGCUGUCACCCUGAAACGGCCACCCCCUUACCAGUGGGACCCCAUGCUGGGUGAGGAUGUUUGGGUUCCUCAAGAAAGGACAGCACAGACUUCAGGGCCCAACCCCUUAAAACUGUCCUCUCUGAUGCUGAGUCAGGGCCAGCACCUGGACGUGUCCCGACUGCCCUUCAUCUCCCCCAAGUCUCCUGCCAGCCCCACUGCCACUUUCCAAACAGGCUAUGGGAUGGGAGUGCCAUAUCCAGGAAGCUAUAACAACCCCCCUUUGCCUGGAGUGCAGGCUCCCUGCUCUCCCAAAGAUGCCCUGUCCCCAACGCAGUUUGCACAACAGGAGCCUGCUGUGGUCCUUCAGCCGCUGUACCCACCCAGCCUCUCCUAUUGCACCCUGCCCCCCAUGUACCCAGGAAGCAGCACGUGCUCUAGUUUACAGCUGCCACCUGUCGCCUUGCAUCCAUGGAGUUCCUACAGCGCCUGCCCGCCCAUGCAGAACCCCCAGGGCACUCUCCCCCCAAAGCCACACUUGGUGGUGGAGAAGCCCCUUGUGUCCCCACCACCUGCCGACCUCCAAAGCCACUUGGGCACAGAGGUGAUGGUAGAGACUGCAGACAACUUCCAGGAAGUCCUCUCCCUGACCGAAAGCCCAGUCCCCCAGCGGACAGAAAAAUUUGGAAAGAAGAACCGGAAGCGCCUGGACAGCCGAGCAGAAGAAGGCAGCGUUCAGGCCAUCACUGAGGGCAAAGUGAAGAAGGAGGCUAGGACUUUGAGUGACUUUAAUUCCCUAAUCUCCAGCCCACACCUGGGGAGAGAGAAGAAGAAAGUGAAGAGUCAGAAAGACCAACUGAAGUCAAAGAAGUUGAAUAAGACAAACGAGUUCCAGGACAGCUCCGAGAGCGAGCCUGAGCUGUUCAUCAGCGGGGAUGAGCUCAUGAACCAGAGCCAGGGCAGCAGAAAGGGCUGGAAAAGCAAGCGCUCCCCACGGGCCGCCGGCGAGCUGGAGGAGGCCAAGUGCCGGCGGGCCAGUGAGAAGGAGGACGGGCGGCUGGGCAGCCAAGGCUUCGUGUACGUGAUGGCCAACAAGCAGCCGCUGUGGAACGAGGCCACCCAGGUCUACCAGCUGGACUUCGGGGGGCGGGUGACCCAGGAGUCCGCCAAGAACUUCCAGAUUGAGUUAGAGGGGCGGCAGGUGAUGCAGUUUGGACGGAUUGAUGGCAGUGCGUACAUUCUAGACUUCCAGUAUCCGUUCUCAGCCGUGCAGGCCUUUGCAGUUGCCCUGGCCAACGUGACUCAGCGCCUCAAAUGAAGAGACUGGUGUGGGGAGGAGAGAGAUGCAGAGAGCCUUUGGAAGAGGUCUUCGGAGAUGCCAGAGGAGCCCUCUAGGGGUCCGAUGCCUGGGAGGACCAGAAGCCAACAGCAAAACUGGAAAAGCCCGGCAGGCCCAGGAGAGGGCGCUGACCUGUGGUCGUCAUUUAUUUGGUUGGGUUUUAUUACCUUUUAUUGUCUGUUCUUCUUUUCUUCUUUCAUUUCAGUGGCAUUUGGAAGCAAAGAGUGCUAGGCACCUGCUGUUCUUUCAGGAAACAGCUUGGCUGUGGUAAUGCUCUACUGGGCCCUUCAGAAUGAAGACAGUCUGCCUUAGAGCCUGCUAUUCUUUUAGACAUAGGGAGGAUGCAUUAUCCUGUAUUCUCCUCCAACAUCACCACUAGCGUAAAAGCAAAAAGCUUUUACAAAACACAGCCAAAAAUUCUCAAGAUGCAGGUUCUUGGGGAAUGGGAUGGGGACAGCAUUUGAUUUACACUGAUUAUGUUACUCCCCAAAAGGUGACUUAAUUAAUAAAGGGCAUUUGGGCAGACACACUGUGUUGGACCAACAAAGUAGGCUCUUUACAGGGGUGUUCUCACCAGGUAGAAAUGCGAUUUGCUCACUGAGGAUGUUGGGGAAGGGACGAAGGGUAAAGAAGAAACUGCACGUAUACACAGGUUCACAUCACUCUGCAGACAGCAAUGUGACUCAGCGUGUGACUUGUAGCAGCAGUACGAGGGCUACACUCCUCUGCUGAGGAUGUCUACAUUGAAAGCCUCCACUAGUUUCAUCGUUUGUCAAAGUUCCGUAGGAUCAGUGAUGGUCAUUCAGCAUGACUGGUUCUGGGAGAAGGUGAGAGACAAAAAUGGAAAGAUCCUGGCCUGUGGUAGUGGUAGCAGUUUUCUCAAAUAAUGUGGUGACAGUCACUAGAUCCUCACAUGCUGAGAAACAGCCUCUACUCUCUCUGCCCCUUUUACUUUUUAAUCUGGAAUGCAUUACUGUAAACAUGAUCUUUCCCAUGAGAUACCAUGUUCUAUGCCUUCCCAUUCUAAAAGUGUGGACAACGCUUGAUUUGAAACCACUCCUUUUCUCCUCUUGGCUACAUUAAAAUUCAGUUGACUACAAAUGCUUUCUAUCAAAUUAGAAAUGUAACCAAAAAAAUGUUAAGUGUUCACCAGGGUAUUAAAAUACAGAGGAGUAUGGUCAAAUCUUUGACAAAAUUUUCAUGAUCUUCUCUAACAAAAAAAGUUGUUUAUUAACUGUACAGACUGUUUACUAAGGAGCUAAACCACUGAGAAAACGUUAUUAAAAUUGUAAUACCUAGGUAGUUGGUUGAUCACAGUUUGUUAAUUGUAUAAAAAAAAAUUACCUAGAAUAUCUCUUCCCACUUCCUCGUCCUCGUGAGAACCUGUGGGCAGUAUUCAAGCCCUGAUGACAAAACCCAGUGUUUUUUGUUGUUGUUUUUUGUUGUUGUUUUUUGUUUUUGUUUUUGUUUUUCUCAGUCUUACCUGUGAUGUUGUUUAGGAUCAGGCCCCUCUCCUGGGCCUGCUGUGCAGGAGCACAGGAACUAUCUGCUGGCGUUGGGUUCCAAAUUUGCAUUUUAUUUGGAAACAGACAAGUAGAAGAUGCUACAGAAAAGUAUUUUCAAAUUUAAACGUUUUUUAAUCCCCUGUUUUAGUUAAAAAAUUGGAAAAGAAACCGACCCAUUUUUUUCCCAGAUCAAGAUGACAUGACAUCACUCCCAAUUCUCUCCAAACCCCAGAGAAAUACUGACGAAGUUUUCUGAUGUGGCAAAGGAUAUUUCCCAUCUAAUACCAGUUUCUCAUUUAUAUUUAACGUAUUGGACCUGAUAUUUUUAGUGGGUGCAUUCUUCCAGAAAGAAUUCAGCAAUGUUAUCAGAAUUAAUUCUUUUAUAUGAGUUUAUGUAGCUUGAUAUGGUGUUUCAGUGCUUAUUGGUUGUGCAAUAAUGGUUAUAGCCUGUUAGAUAAUCUAAAUGCAAUUCCCCUGUUUUGUCGUUUAGGAGAUAAUUAUUUAUCUUGCUUUUCAUAGUGUUCUUAGGAAUUAUUUUGUUGUUACGUUUUGGUGAGUUAUACCCAUUUUAUUUAUUUAGAAAAAUAGUAUCUUUGUUAACGACUUACAUGGUCACAGUAUAUUUUGCUGCAAGAAAUAAAGAGGAUAUGAUAGAAGGUUUUUUUUUUUUUUUUUUUUUUUUUUUGAGACGGAGUCCCACUCUUGUCGCCCAACUAGAGUGUAGUGGCACAAUCUCGGCUCCCCACAACCUCUGACUCCAGGGUUCAGGUGAUUAUUUUGCCUCAGCCUCCCAAGCAGCUGGGAUUAUAGACACCCGCCAACACGCCAGGCUAAUGUUUUUGUAUUUUUAAUAGAGAUGGGGUUUUGCCAUGUUGGCCAGGCUGGUCUUGAACUCCUGACCUCAGGUGAUCCGCCCGCCUCGGCCUCCCAAAGUGCUGGGAUUACAGACGUGAGCCACCACUCCCGGCCCAUAGAAGGUUUUUUGCUGGAUAAUUUGUAACUUUUCUAAUUGGGAAAAAAUUCCUAUUAAUCACUUAAAAAUUUUUUUUUGUAUUUUGUGUUAUUGAUUAUAUACAAAGGAGACUUUUUUUUUGAGAUAACACUCAAAUAGUAUUCUCUUCUUUUGAAAAUUUUAUUUUUAUCUGAAAAUAACAGUUGAUCUGAAAUAAAAAGGGGAGACCUAUUAGAAUGAGAGUAGCCAAGGAAAGAGUUACUAGGUAAUAAGCUUCACUUUUUGUGUUCUAAUUGUUUUUGAGAUAUAAAGACCCUGAAAAAGCCCAUUUUAGAACCUGUUUAAUAAGAGCAAAUAUAGGGGAAAAUCUUUGAAAUGAAAGCUACAAAUACAUGUGAGAAGAAAAAAAUGGAUUUUUUUAGCAAAUAAUUAACUAAGCUUCUAAAUGCCUAGCUCCCUCCCCCAAAGGCGCUUUCCCCCGAUGGAGGCACAGGCUUCUGUCUCGGAUGUUUGGCGCACGUGAGUUUGUAUGAGUUUGUACCGGAGUGACCCCGGCAGCCACUGCCCACCUCCCCUCUACCCAGGGGCCUGAAAAGAGGGGCUGCCCUCCUGCGCCAAGGCAGACACAAGCUGCGGGCUGUGCGGUCCUAGUAGUGUGACGUUUCAGUUAAUAGUGGUGGUCUUAUUUUCAACUAUGCUUUCAUUCAGUCAGUCUCUGUUGACUAAAUACGACGAAAAUUCAUACUUUAUGCAGGAGAUUUCUAAAAAUUUAAUGUUUAUUAAUAGUUUAUGAAUAUCAAGAUACCUCAUUGAAUCCCUAAAUUUAAAAGCAGUCCAGUAAAAGGUUAACUGUAUAAAGAAUCUAUGACUUUUUGAGGGAAGUGUGAUAUAUUAACAAAUAUAACCAAUUCUAAAUUUGUUUUAGCUCUAACCUCAUCAAACCAAAGGCACAGAUUUGUGUACAAUAUACCCAUUGAAUGUAUAUCCUGAGAAAAAUUGGGGCCAAAGAAGCAGGAAAAUCUCAAAGCUCUAAUGGCAGCAUAAAUCAAAGAAUUUCACAGGCUAGUGUUUUUAUCCAUAGCCAUUGCUCCCUUGUCAAGUGUCUCACAAGGACAUGGAAGAAUGUGUUAUGUUCAUCUUGUAAUCAUAGCAAAAAGUCUGCAAACCCCAGGGUCAAGCCUGCUCUGCCACAGGGUUGGAUGGUGACCUUGGGCAAGUCCCUGGGGCUGGCUAGGCCUCCACUUGUCCAUCUGUGAAAUGAAAGGAUCAGCCUGGACAGCCCUCUAAACUCCCUUACAGCUCUCAGCCUAAGAGCGCAGCACUGAACAGCCUCAUCAUUCCACUUUUCAUGGGAAAUAUAUUUCACACCAUUGCCUUUGUGUAGAGAAAUAUUUCUUUUCCUGUGUUAAUGAGCUAUGUACUGAAUAUAAACCAGUGCAUUUAAAGUAAUAUCUUUUGUGCACCUCUAAAUGUGUUUGGAAUUGUGUUUGUUCUCAUAGAAUAUACAAAAGUACUGAUUCUAGGUAAGAAGGAGUCUCCACGGGUGUGCCCUGCUCAGCUGGAUGUCCAUGAGAACAGCCAUGAAAUAAGUCACUACUUGUCCCCAAAACCACAGGAAUAUAUACCUAGGUCACCUCAAAUUCCUGAGUGUGCUCUGCCAUGUUACACGGUCUUCAAAUUGAAAAGGUUUCUUGAAAAGGAAAGUUUGGCCCAGCAACUGGAGAAGGAGUCCAUGGUGUCGCUGUGUGCCUGUAUCAUUUGGCCAAGUCAAUGGUUGUAAGCAAAGUUAGUGGAGACAAAAAUGUGUCCAAAAUGUCGUUUGAGUUCCUGGGAUUUCUGUAAUAGCACACAACUCAGAACUCUUCAGCAUUUGUGUGAUUCCUUACCUCUGGCUGAUAAAACUCUAAUGGGUUGUGGCUUACUUUGUUUCCAUUUUCUUUGGCUUUGUGCAAUUUUUGUGUAACUUUACUUGUACCUAUAUUUUCUGUUUACAGUUCUUUUUAAGGGGAGGGGUAGGGUUCUAAGAUCUUGUUGUUUAUUGUAGAUAAAAAUUUUUUCGUGUUGUAGAAAAGCAUGGGUUAUGCGUUUGACUGAAAAAGACACUGUAUUAUUUACCAAAGGGGUAUUGUUUUUGCAUUUGUUUAUAAAUGCAUUAUUUUGGUACUGUAAAUUUGGACAUAAUUUCUGAGUUUAUUACUACUGGCAUUUUCUUUUUCCCUUUUUUUUUUUUUUAACCGUAAGUGCACGAUGCAGGUGCAUAGGCCCCAGACCAAACUAGACCACCAGCAUGUUCAUGUCCAGACCUCGGCAGUGGCGUGCACUGCUUGUGCACCUCAGUUCCUCCAGUGUUGGUUUGUUUGUUUUUUAAUUCAGCAUCCUGCUGGUUUUACUUUCCAAGCAAGAUCUGUUGCGACUCCCAAAUGCGUUUUAAUGAGCUCAUCCUUAUUUGCCUUUCUUCUUACGUAUUUUGUGUAUUAGAUUGUGCAGGAGAUAUUCUAGAAGGCAUUAAUGGUUUGCAUUCAAAACGAUGUGGUUUGUCCAAGUUAUUUUCUGUCUUUAUUACUGAGACGGAUUAAUCUCCUUAUUUUUUUCUUGAUGAUUUGAAGUUGUAAGAGUUGUCCAGCUAUUGCUUAAUAAAAUUUUGCAGAUCAAAAAA